AUGUGUGUGUGUGUGCGUGUAAGUAUAUACAUUGUGGGGGAGAGAGAAAGGGAGACAGAGAGAGAAGGAAAUAGAAAUGCAGUAAAAUGGUGACAUUUGGGGAAUCUGGGUGAAGGGUAUACAGGAAUUCUUUAUGCUGUUCUUGCAACUUUUAGGUCAAAAAUAUUUUGUUUCAUUUUGUUUUGUUUUGGAGUGUAAAAUAAUCUAUCAAUGGAAAAGAAUGAAUUAUCUUAAAGAUUGAUGUGCCGUUGUGUCAUUUUUCAGCCACUUGUCAGGCUUAGUCCAGGGUUGCUUUGGGAGCCCUUCCCAUGCACACCCAGGAAUGAUUCCAGAGAAUAGUUCCAGUCAGUUGAAUGCUAUGGGAGCUUCUAGGUGCAGGAAGUCGUGGCUUUCACAUGUUCCAUUUUCUUCAGUCCUUUGCUCAUUCUCAGGUACACUCUCCAUUAAAUUGAACAAUUCCAUAAAAGAUAGAUUGCACUACAGCCAACUUCUGCCCAGCCUUUUCCAAUUAGCAGAUUCAAAUUAGGAAGAUUUAAUUGCAAUUUGGAUUGAAUUCUGUCCCUCAGCAGUCAAGUCAAUUUCAUUUAAUUCAAUUCAGCACACACGGAGUACUCAGGGCCCUUGCAUAUGGCUGAGUGAUUGGAACACACACAAGGGCCUACAGGGAAGUGGGACUGAACAGGUGACAUAGGUGGGACUCAUCCUGGGGAGAUGGCAGGAGGAGCAGCACAGGUGCUGGCCCUGUCCUCAGCUUUCUUUAUAGAGCCAAACCUCCUUGUCUUUCUUAAUCAUUUAAACCAGUCUGCAUUCCUGACCACUACCUGCCCCAAGAAACAGAAAGAAGGAGGCUCCGGGAGGCUGGUCCCUGCCCUAGCAGGGGAUGCUAGGAGGCCCUGCCUAGAGGCCCGCCUGGUCCACCCUUGGGCUCUUUCUGCUUGUUUUGUUCCCACUUCCCAAGUAGGAUGCUGAUUCUCCUCCCUUGUAAUUAGCUCUGCUCCAGCGGGGGCCAGCCUAGUGGCGCCGAGGGGUUUUGUGAUUGAUUGUGCUAACUGCAUCCCAGCCCUCUUUUCUAGAGAGGCUGCUUCUGCCAGGAGAUAGGCAGCCUGGUAAUUGGAUGGCAGGAAAUGCAUUAUAGGAAGGGCUACUCUCAUCCUCUGCAAGGAGCCCUGGGGGAGUGUGUCUGUUGCAUCCCCUAUCCCCUUUAGAGAACCAUCAGAGACCACAGACUUCUGCCCUAGGUCAUUCCAGAAACUGGGCUGCAAGCCCAUGUCCAGCCCAAGGUCGUCCACCCCCUGAGGUUACCCUGGCCUUUUUUCCUACUUUGGGAUAUCUUAACCCAACCCAAGCAGCUUCUCUCAGCUGGGAACCCUGGCCUGAGAGUGUGUGGAAGCCUUGGGGGAUACAUCCCAAACCCCUCUCUUUCUUGCCCAUGCCUAAUAACUUGAUCCUGACCUUAAGCCGCAACCCAGGGCCUGAGUUCUUUUCACUCUCCUUCUUGGACUCAGUCCUGGCUUCUCAGUUCUAACUCUGCUCCCCAUUGUGGACUAUACCCCACUCUGUCACAGCUGCAGCCCUGCCUAGGUGGAGGUCUCUAAGUACCUGGGACCUGUGGGCAGAGGGUGGGUGGAGGGUGAGCACCUCCGAUUGUCCUUUCCCCUCCGGGCAACCUUGCCUCAGCAAAGCUCCCAAAGCUCCCUGAGCCUGGAGUCACCCAUAGGAUGGUGCUGGCACUCGUAGGGCCAGAUUCUGGGAAGAACUUAGGGUCUGUACAGCAACCAGACCACACCAUGUUCAAGAACAUUAAAAGUGGAAAAUAAAGUUCAGCGUGAUGUUUAGAUACAAAGGCCAAAAAUGACACAUUGGCACAAGAAAUCUCCAAAACACAGUUCUGGGUUAACCCUGUGGCUUUAGGUCUGUGGGAUAUUCCUGUGACCCCUUUAGACACUUAGCAAGUUCUUACAGGCUGGUGGCAACAGCAAAGGCUGGAGACACUGCUGCCUUAGGGGCUAAUUUCUCUUUGAGUCAGGUCCUGGUCAGACUUCUUUAGGGUUCGAGGAACCACAUCCCCUGUUGGGGUAGCCCAGAUCCAUCAUGAGAGCCCACCCAGGCCCACCUAGGGCAGACCAUCCCACCCAUUUGAGGGACAAGGUGCCUCUUGCUUUUCCAGUUAGCAUUCUUAGGAUUGGGAUGACUCUGUUCCAAGUUCCUUGGGACUUUGCUUUGGUAGAAUUCCUUGAACAUUUGUUUUGAAUUUGUUAGGCUCCCUGAGACUUCUGGGUAAAUGCUGAAAAUCAGAGAUUCUGCCAUGUGAGGCAGUGCAAUGGAUUGAGCCCAGGCAAGGGUGUGAAACCCUGAUGGUCCCAACUGGACAGCCAAGGUCCAUGAAUAAGGCACUGUCCUUCUGCAGGCCUCAGAUGCACCUGUGAAUAUGAGGGGCUGACCUAGUGGAUUUCUAAGUUUGCAUCCAACUGGCUCCAAGAGUUUAGUUCAUUUCCCAAGUGACAGGCUCAUCAUGAGCUGUUCCAGGGAUUCGGGCUGAUAAUGGCUUUUUGCAUCUGUGUAGUGCUCUACAAAGAGUUUUCACCUGCAUUUUCUCAUUUGAUGCUCCAACAUUACCAUGAGGAGCUACUGUUAUCAUCAUCUUAGAGAUGAGGCUCAAAGAAGUGAAUUAGCUAGAGAGGGUCUCACAGCUAAGAAGGGAUGGACUUGGGACAAGGACCUGGGUCUUCUGACAGCUGCUGCUGUUCAGGCUGUGGUGUGCAUGGAGUCUGUGAGAGUGACUGGCAGUCCUUCCUGCCCGUAGCAGCUGGACCUGGGCUGUGCAAAGAGGAGGAUGGGGCCAGAUGCCAGGGACCAUCAGAGACCAUCAGAGAGCUCCUGCCAACUCUCCAGGGCUCAUACUCUCAUGAGCGUAACCCAGGGAUCUCAGUGUGGAUGCUGGCUUGAGUCCUGCUCAGUUCCAGGUGCGGCCCAUCCCUCAGCACUAUCAGCAUUACCUAGCCACUCCUCGAAUGCACCACUUUCCCAGAAACUCCUCCUCCACACAGAUGGUCGUCCAUGAAAUCCGAAACUACCCUUACCCUCAGCUUCACUUCCUUGCUCUCCAGGGACUAAAUCCCAGCAGACACACCUCCGCCGUACGGGAGAGCUAUGAGGAGCUGCUGCAGCUCGAGGACAGGUUGGGUAAUGUGACUCGGGGAGCUGUACAGAACACCAUUGAGAGGUUCACCUUCCCCCACAAGUAUAAGAAGCGAAGACCCCAGGAUGGCAAGGGCAAGAAGGAUGAGGGGGAGGAGUCAGACACAGAUGAGAAAUGCACAAUUUGUCUGUCUAUGCUGGAAGAUGGAGAAGAUGUGAGACGCCUACCCUGUAUGCAUCUCUUUCACCAACUGUGCGUGGACCAGUGGCUCGCCAUGAGCAAGAAAUGCCCCAUCUGCCGAGUGGACAUUGAGACACAACUGGGAGCCGACAGCUGAGGGAGGAAUUAGCCAGUGGACACCCCAUUUCCUUCACCAGGUCCCCCCACGGCCAUAGCCCUUGCAGCCAAACUUUGCCUUCUGAGCCAUUUGACGUAGAGGAAAAGCCUGCAAGCACAUUUUGUGGAAAGAGGAGUUGGUGGUAUCGGUGUCGAGGGAGAGGAGGGGGUUGGGGAGGACCCACCUCUCCAGAAUGGCGACUGUCCCCAUCCGCCUGGCUGAGCAGGAGAGAGGGAGCUGGCGGUGCCCAGCGCAAGGGCGGGAAGGAGGGGCCCAGGCUGCGGAGAACCCAGGUGGGAUCCUGAAGGCACUAGCUGACAGACGGGCCCCUCAAUCCUGUCCUCUGAAGGAUUGUAUAUAUACCUCUCGACCACGUAGGAACCAUGUAGGGGUCUCUAGCUAUUUCUGUGGAUGGCAGCCGGAGCAUGUUAGCUUAAGAAAAAUGUUGUGUGUGGUGCUCUAGUCAUCUUGUGGUGGACAUGUCGCUAUUACCGAAUUCGCACCAAAUAUUUCUCAUUGAGUUUCUUGUUUUGGUGCCUGACCGAACCAACGACAGCCCCAAUCUUCCCGUCUUUAUGAGAGAAAAGGAAAAAGGAAUCAAAGGUGGAAGAAAAAAAAAGCCAAAUUCUGUUUACGGUGAAAAAGGAUUUUGUUUUUCACCCAAUUUGGGAGGCGGGAGGGGGGGGUUCUCGUUUUAUUUUUGUUUUUGUUUUUACCUUGGCUUUUGUUUUUCUCAUGUUUACAGUGCACGGAGUGUGGAAGGGGGUCUAGGAGAGGGAGAGCUGGAAAAGGAGCUGAUGGGGUCUUAUCCUGGCCUCUGAGGGUUCAGCGGAGGUGAGGAAGGCAGCAGAGCUCCAGCAGGUGAAGGGAGAGUUCAUCUAGGCGGGGCUCCCCAGGCCCAGGGCUCAACUUCAUGGCCCCAGCUAUAUCCCCCCAGUUCCACACUAAACCAGGGAGGGCUCGGCCCUCAGCUACUGGUACCCAAUGUGUUCCUGGGAGCCGAGAGACCCAUGGUCACUCCAACUCCUUCCUUUAGGCUGUGCUCUUGCCUGUCACAAAGAGGCAACGUAGCCACUGCCUCCCUAUGCAAAAAAUUAACCAGAUGAUGCAGAUAAGACAGCAUAGGUGAUGGCUGCUUGGUCUUGGCCACAGUGCUCUCAGCCAGCACUAAGGGCUGAGGUCAAUACCGCAGACCUUGGGGAGGAAGCUGAGCAUCCCCCGGGAUGUCUCCAGUCCUGACACAGUCCCUCAGAGAUGGCCCUGGCUCUGAGGUCACAUCAGCUAGGUUUGGGAGGCCCCUCAGCUUGGUUUGGGAGUGCCCGUGUUCCUGGUCUCUGGCUGCUUCUCUGACUCUUUGAUAACCUUGGGCAAGUCCCUUUCUUUCUCUGUGCCUCAGUUUCCUUCUCCUUUGAGGGGGGAGAGAGAACAGUGCAGCCCCAUUUCCGGUCCUGCUACCUCACCUAGAUGUUGUGAGGAUUCAUAUUCUCUGUCCAGCGUGUUCUAUGCUCUCUUCUGAGAACCUUGUGGGGUGUCGGGAUGGGGGUGCUGGGAGACACAGACCUGAUACAGUAUGUCUUUCUGCACCACCUCACAAUUUUCCUGAACCCCAAAGGGAGCAGAGAGAUAAGAGGACAGAAGAAUGGAGAUGGGAAAAUCCACCAAAUUCCAACCCAAACCCAACUUUCUUUCUCCCUAUGUGGAAGACACCAGAUUAGCUGGAAUUCUGCCACCUUCCUUUGUGCCCCACCCCCCACUGUUCCCUCAUUUGCACUGCUCUGUAAGCCUCCCCCUCACCUCCAUUCAUAACCCAGUCUCAAUGCCCUCGUAUCAAUAAGACCGGGGUAAGGGGGACAGGAUACUUGUCACAUAUUUGAAGAAAUUCCAUACAGUGAAGGAAAUUUGAGUCUGUAUUGCUGCUACAAGGGUAAAACCAGGACCAAUGGGUAAAAGUAACAGGCGGGCAGAUUUUGGCUUGAGGAAGAGCUUCUAGCACGACUGGUUCAUGCGGGAAUAGCUGCUCUGGCCACCUGCAGGCAGAAAGUGGGGGAAGUGGCUCCUGGCAGGAGAUUUCUCCCAGCACUAAUAUCCUGGUGUUCUAUAAAAUCUUUAUUGAGUGCCUACCGGUGCAGGCGCUGGGAGAGACAAUAGCUUUGAGGAGCUCACAAUCUAGCUGAGGAGACAAGACACAUCCAAUGCUGCAAAAAUGGUGAAUAACCUGAUUCAGGGUUAGCAGCAAUGAGUAUCACAGCGUCCAACUCAGUAGCUCCAGUGUAUGAAAAUGUCUCCAGGGCUAAAGGCUGGAGAUCUCACCAGUGGGGAAAGUACAUCUGAGUCAGGAUUUUGGGGGAAAGCUAGUUACUGAUAGCCACAGGAAGUUGAGACUUCUGCCCCAUUCUCUCCAAUGGCUGGGUGAAAACCAAGAAUUCAUCGGAAGAUGGCUUUGGCCUGGAGGUAGCUAGGGUGGUCUAGGAAGCUCACUCCUCUCUUAGUCUCAGUCUUUCAUUCUUUCUGCUGAGACUGGCCUGAAAGGCUGGCAAGUGGGAGGGAGUCAGUGGGGAGGCCAGGAUAGAACUAGAGCUGGUGUCCCAGGUUCCAGUCUGGGCUCUUCACUGACAAAGUGGGCAACACUAGAAACUUCCCUUUGUCUCUCUGGGCCUUAGUUUCCUCAGUUACAACCUAAGGAGGUUGGAUUGGAUGCUUGCUAAUUUCCUUCUGACACUCACACUCCCUAACAUCAACACAUCUUCAAGGCGGCAGAGCUGUGCGCCCACCCAGCUAUUGAAAAGGACUUUCUGUGGGCACACACUCUGUUUCAGACUGGGCUGGGGGCACACGUGCUGGGUGAGACAGUGGGCCCUCGUCCCCUCCCCCCUCCCAAUUCUCUGCCCCAGGCUAAUAUUAGGGACUGGGGAGGGGACCACCAGAGGGGAGAGGGAAGCUGCUUACUUUGGGGGUAGACCCUGAAGCCCCUCCUCCUUCCCCCACAGAUGGGGACAGGAGGUGAUGGGGUGCUCAGAACCCUGCAGCUCCCACUUCUUUAGCCGGGCAGCUGUUUGGGGGACAAGAGAGGGCCAGGGUCUGUGCUUCUGCUCCCGGCACUGGUCAGGGAGUCUGGGAAGAGUGGAGAAGAGGCAGGGUCAGGCCUCAGCAUCUCACAUCCACCACCUCCAGGAGGGGAGACCACUGGUAAGUCCUCCUCCUGCUCAACUCAAGGGACUCAGACCCUUUCUUGACUGAGACGCAUGAGUGCCUUCUGGGGUGAGAGCAGCCCCAGGGUUUAAGUUGGGCGUCCUAGCAGCUGCAGCAGCUGUGCCGCCGCGGGUCCACCGAGGACGCCAAUCAAUCAACCCAACACCACAAGCUUGGUUGGGUGCAAGCAGAGGGUGAGCAGGGGCUGCCCCUCCACCUGGCCAGGACCCCCUUCGGCACCCAGUUGCCCUUGGCCACCACCUGUGGCAGGACUCAAGCUCCUCUUCUGCAAAUGUUCCCAGCCUCCGUGCAAGUAUUCUUAACUCUUUACGCCUAAUGAACAAGCACAGUUUUUCAAUGGUGAAGAAAAAAGCACCAGACUUUUUUUCUUUUUUUCCUAAAGAAAUCCCCUAAGCCCCCCGCCUGUAGGCGGGACAAACACUCCCUGCGUGGGGCUGUAGCAACGUCUGUCAGGCCCCCUUGUGUUUCAUCUCCUGCGCGCGUAGAGCAAAUGCUAGAGCGAUUUCAGCUGAUAGAAAAACAAAAAUGAAAAAAAAAACACAAAAAACAAAAAACAUGGCACGUUGCUAGUUUACAGGGUUUUGUGAGUUUAAAUGCCUUAUAUUUAACAAUCAUAAUUUAUGACUAACUUGUAGAUAUCGUGGGUUCUUAUUUAAUUAUUUUUAUAGUUGUUUUGCAUUUUUAAUUAUAAUUUAUUUAUUUAGAAAGGAUACUAAUUUUUUUUAUUACUCCUAUUACCUCAUUUUGGCGUUGUUUCUGGGAGUGGAAUGCUUUGCAUGCAUUGGUACGAUGACAAACAACUACGAAUACAAAAAAAAAAUUUAAAUAAAAUUCUGCAAACUUUAUUUCGUCCGAACUAUCAGGGUGUGUGAUUGCAAGCUGUCCUACCGUGGUGCUGGCCUCUUUGGAUACAUUCCAUACGAAAUGCAAACCUUUGAUUCUGUAUGCUGUGAUCUAGUGAAAAACUCCAAUAUAGUGACUGUAUUUAGCACAUAUAUAAAUAUAAUUUGCACUUGUCAGCAGACUGGGGUAAUCCUUUCACUUGCUACACUUGGCACCCCCCCGCCCCCACCACAACCCUGCCUCUCCAUCAUGAACCUGCCUUUCCUCCUCCCUCGCUCCUCCCACAACCUCAGCCCACCCAGCCGGUAUCCUCUGAGGAAAGUCUUGGGGCACUAGAGGCCACUGUCUCCACCUGGCCUCCAACUCCAGAAUUGGAGCCCUCCAGACAUUACAAGAGGAACAUCAGAGAGCCAAAAAGCCUGACUUCUUAGAAGGAGCCCUGGACUGGGGAGCCGGGAGGCUCAGGUUUUCAAAUCUGCUCCAUGACAGACGUCCCAAUGACCUUGAGCAAGUCCCUUGGCCCCUGAGUCUCAGUUUUCUGGGUGGGGUGAGUGAGGAGAACUGGGAGAUCUUUAGGGUCCCUUAGAUUCAAGUAGAAUGUGACACAGAUCCCGUGGGAAACCACUGUGCUGUGCUGUCUCACCUUCUGAGGAGAGAAGAAAGAGGGAGAAAAGGCAGGGCAUGGUGGCUCACGCCUGUAAUCCCAGCACUUUGUGAGGCCAAGGUGGGCAGAUCACUUGAGAUCAGGAGUUUGAGACCAGCCUGGCCAACAUGGUGAAACCCUGUCUCUACUAAAAAUACAAAAAUUAGCUGGGCGUGGUGGUAGGCGUCUGUAAUCCCAGCUACUCGGGAGGCUGAGGCAGGAGAAUGGCUUGAACCCAGGAGACGGAGGUUGCAGUGAGCUGGGAGCGUGCACCACUGCACUCUAGCCUGGGUGAUAAGAACAAAACUCAGUCCAAAAAAAAAAAAAAAAAAAAAGAGGGAAAGAGGGAGAAAGGAUUGGGAGGAGAAAAGGAGAGCAAAGAAGAAGAGAAGAAUAGAGAGAGUGAGCUGAGAAUUUGAGCUUGCUCAGAGUUGACUUUCGGGAGGGUUUUUGUCCUAUAAUAUGUGGCAUCCUGUGGGUGACAGGGAGGUGAGUUAGGUGGACACGUAUAGGACGUGCCCUUUCAUAAGGCUUGGGCAGUCAUUUGGCGAGUGAGCUGAAAUCCAUGUCUUGUUAGAGAUAGGGAUGGGGUAGGCAGAAAGGAGCUCCAAACUAUGGGUUUGGGAUUGGCACCCCUAUCCUAUCAUCACCCAGAGUCUUCAUUGUUGAGAUGCUGCCCAUGGAAAACAGAUUGGGACAUAGAUUUUGGAAUCAAGGUCUCUGCUCCUGGCAUCUCCUCUGUGCGUCUCCCUCUGCCUUUGCUCCCUGGGGACUGUGGGCAGGAGGAGCUUCUUCGGAGGACCGGGAGUGGGCCUCCAGUCCCCCUGCCCCUGUAGAGGAAUAAUGAGGGAGGACAUGGGGAAGUCACUGUCAAAGGCUGGCACAGCUGUGAGCCCAAUGCCUCUGAGCGAAAAGGAGAGAGAGGGAGUUCACGCCCCUGAGAGUAGCCCCCUGAGCCGGCUGGGACCUGGACUGCCUGCUUUCCUCCUGCCUCUUCCCCUUUCCCUCCUUCACAGCUUAUCCUCCUUCUUCCCUCUUUACAUCACUGCCUUUACCUGGUGGGGAUGAGGCCCCAUGGGGAAGGUGCUGAUGUGGAGGGAGGAAGUGGAGACCGAGAUUCGCCAUACUGCCCAGGGAGGCUGUGUGAGAACUGGGCUGUGUAUGGUCCCUAAAGCCUCAACUCUGCCCCAGCUGGGCGAUGGGUGCCCCUCUCUGGGCUUCCUGCCUAGCUUCCCCUUCUGCCUCCAGCCUGGAGCCUUGCUUUCCCUGGAGACAAGCCCGUGGAGUCCCCCACCACACUGGAGGGAGCACGACCACCACACUGCUGGGCCUGGCAGACACCACAUCUUUGGCAGGGCUCCUGGACGGGCAUGCCUUAUGCUGCUCUGCAGGGUCAGAGUGGAAAGGGGCCCUUUGCCCUGGCUGGCCUGUGCCCUCACCCUUGAGCCCCUCCCCCCACUCCACCCCUGGCCUCGGAUGCGGCUAAUUUCUCAGCCAUGGAGCCAGCUGCACCAGCCCUCGAGGGGGUAAUUUUGUUGCCCCUGGCAAGUGAAAGGAUUAUCCUCAGUGUUGAUUGUCCUUUUUUGUAAUCCUCCUGCUGUUCUGUUCUGUUGUGCUGUGCAACAUUUUGCUACAUAGACUAUUUUAUAGCAGAAAGCUAGAAGAAUAUUUAUUAUGAAUAUUAAAGCAAUAGUGCAUCAAUGAAAAGGCGGAGACAUUAGGAAUUGUGUAAAUGCUUAGAUUCACUUUUGGUGGAUUUUUUGUACUUUAUUUAUAACUAAUAAAAAUGAACUGCAUUGCUAACUACA